GGCACUUCCGUGGCUUCGGGCGGGUGAGUAUGGGGAGUGCGCGCGGCGUCCAGGAGUCGGGACUGGGCUCCCGCCUACGGCCGCCCUCCCGCCGGGGGGCCAGCGCGGUCCUCCGGGGCGCCCCCUGGAGGAUUUGGGGUGGGGGAAGGAAAAGGAGAGUAUUAUCGAAUAUUCUCCUAAUAUUGAUGUUCGGGGUGCGGAUAUGUGUGGACAGGCAGGAGUCGGCAAAUGGGUUCAAAUGGAAGCUUUAACAAAGAAAGGCCCUGGAGGUCACAAUCACAUUGAGCCAAAACGCAUCCAGUGUUUUCUCCAGUUACAAAUAAAACGAAUAUGCCCAUGCUGCUACCACAUCCUCACCAGCAUUUCCUAAAAGGCCUUUUAAGAGCACCUUUCCGAUGUUACCACUUCAUCUUUCACUCAAGUACUCAUCUCGGAUCAGGAAUCCCAUGUGCUCAGCCGUUUAAUUCUCUUGGACUCCAUUGUACAAAGUGGAUGCUGCUGUCAGAUGGCUUAAAGAGAAAAUUAUGUGUACAAACAACCUUAAAGGACCACACAGAAGGACUUUCUGAUAAAGAGCAAAGAUUUGUGGAUAAACUUUAUACUGGUUUAAUCCAAGGGCAAAGGGCCUGUUUAGCAGAGGCCAUAACUCUUGUAGAAUCAACUCACAGCAGGAAAAAGGAGUUAGCCCAGGUGCUUCUUCAGAAAGUAUUACUUUACCACAGAGAACAAGAACAAUCAAAUAAAGGAAAACCACUAGCAUUUCGAGUAGGAUUGUCUGGGCCCCCUGGUGCUGGAAAAUCAACAUUUAUAGAAUAUUUUGGAAAAAUGCUUACUGAGAGAGGGCACAAAUUAUCUGUGCUAGCUGUGGACCCUUCUUCUUGUACUAGUGGUGGAUCACUCUUAGGUGAUAAAACCCGAAUGACUGAGUUAUCAAGAGAUAUGAAUGCAUACAUCAGGCCAUCUCCUACUAGAGGAACUUUAGGAGGCGUGACAAGGACCACAAAUGAAGCUAUUCUGUUGUGUGAAGGAGCGGGAUAUGACAUAAUUCUUAUUGAAACCGUUGGUGUGGGUCAGUCGGAGUUUGCUGUUGCUGACAUGGUUGACAUGUUUGUUUUACUACUGCCACCAGCAGGAGGAGAUGAGCUGCAGGGUAUCAAAAGGGGUAUAAUCGAGAUGGCAGAUCUGGUAGCUGUAACUAAAUCUGAUGGAGACUUGAUUGUGCCAGCUCGAAGGAUACAAGCGGAAUAUGUGAGUGCACUGAAAUUACUCCGCAAACGUUCACAAGUCUGGAAACCAAAGGUAAUUCGUAUUUCUGCCCGAAGUGGAGAGGGGAUCUCUGAAAUGUGGGAUAAAAUGAAAGAUUUCCAGGACCUAAUGCUUGCCAGUGGGGAGCUGACUGCCAAACGACGGAAGCAACAGAAAGUUUGGAUGUGGAAUCUCAUUCAGGAAAGUGUGUUAGAGCAUUUCAGGACCCACCCCACAGUCCGGGAACAGAUUCCACUUCUGGAACAAAAGGUUCUCAUUGGGGCCCUGUCCCCAGGACUAGCAGCAGACUUCUUGUUAAAAGCUUUUAAAAGCAGAGACUAAUAAAAUUCAUCCUGUAUAAUAAUUUUACAUAUCAUUUCAUAAAGUAUUUUAAUAGAAAAAUCACUUGUAUGCUUAUAUUUUCAGUAAUUAUUGUAUGGUGCUCUUGUCUUCUUUGUUUGUGACCCAUGCUUGAAAACUUGAAGGAAGUUAGAUAUGAAUGGCAAAAGUUAGGCAGUAUUUAUAAGGUACCUGUUUUAUGUUACUGAUAUCUGUUUCCUUCUCUUCUUAUACCCUGGCAUGGUGGCCUGUAGGGUAGUUUCUUCUUAAUAGUCAAGAACAGAGAAAGCUGAGGAGAGCAGAAAAUAUCUUGCACUUUAAAAUGCUUAUUUUGAUUCCAUAUUAUCUGAAUUUCCAGAGAGGAUGUAAACAAGAGUGACCAUAUUUUUGGAGUCCUUCUUGAAGCCAGAACAACACACAGUGGGUUGCUAAGAGCCGACAAUCAUAAUUGACAUUUAGUGUACCAGAUUAUUCUAAGAAUUUCUGAAAUUACCAUGUACAUGAGUAAUGAAACAACUGGAAUAAUGUGAUGAUGUGAACACAAUUUUAAAGUCUGCUUGUCUGGAUUUGCAGGUACCCUUCCGCCACCCCCCAACAUGAUAGGUAAGAGAGCAAAAGGGAACUGGGAAAAAUCAGCUACAAAUAAAAUGGGUGACUAAUCCCCAGUUCUUGGACCCAUUAUAUUUGUAGCCAAUUGGAGUAAACCCCUAAAAGACAAAGUGAGGUCAGAAUGAUUCAAGGAUUAUUCAGUUUGAAGACUACCAAAGGCUUUUGCUUCUCUUCUUCCUUGGCCAUUUCACUUCAUUUUAGUAUUUUAAAAAUCUUUUUUCUUGAUGGUGAACAAGUUUUGUCCUAUGCUAUGGAGGAGGCAUAGCACAGUGAUUAAGAGCUUGGGCUCUGUAGUUGGACUAUGUGGGUUUAAACUUUAAACCCAGAUCAAUUGUAUAUUAGCUACAUGAGCUAAUCUCUUUAAGCUUCCAUUUCCUCCCUGGUAAAAUGAAAUUGGCAAAUAACUUUCUAAGGUUAGUGAAGAUAGGAAAUACUCGAAGGCUGCUUACUAUCCUUAUUACAUUAAAGUUAUGGGUAUCUUGAAACUACAAACCUGAUGUAUAAUUUCAGUUUUCUCUCAUGGUCUUGUUACUACCAUCAUACUCUUGAUAUUUUAGGAUACUUUAGGAUUACCUUUGAAGAACCCUUUCUAGUUAAUUCUUUGAAUAUGUUUUAUACUUAUUUGAUGGUAGUUGUAACUGUGUACAUUUGAAUAAAAUUUCUAACCAUAAAAUUUCGCCAUUGCACAAAAAGCCUUUAUAGAAGUUUCUAACAUAUUCUAUUCUGAACCCUGUAGAAUAUUUUAUGUAGUAUAGCAGCUUGCAUUGUUACUUACUGUACUGGAAUCAAACCUCUUGAGCAUUAUUUUAACAAACAUCCCUUUACAUUUUUUGGAAAGAUUUUUAGUACUCCAUUGGCAUAGCUAUUUCAUACAAGGAUUAGGAGAAACUUUGAAAGGUUAUCCACUUGACUUUUCUGAUUUUAGAAAGGACUACCAUUAAACCACCCUAUCAGACAAAAAAAACUGGUUUUUAGAAACCUGAGAGAAGGAAUUUUAUAAUUUCCCUGAGUAAGCUGUUACAGGGAAUAACAAAUCUCCUGCCACAUGUGGCACAGUGUAAGUAAUGCUGGAGCACACAUACUGCAUUGUAAAGAAGGUAGGAAAGGUGGGGGGACUUUUGUUAGCUUUAAUUUUAAGGCUAAAAGCAUUUCUUCUCAGUUUGAACUACUUUUAAAUGUUAUAAAUGUCAUCAUAAAAAUCAUUAGAAAACUCAUUUCUCCUUAUGUUGUCGUUGUACCAUUGGGUAUUGUAUAGAGACCAAUUUCUAAGAGAUUUUUUCACCUCUGUUUCUGUUAUUUGCUAUACUGGAGGUAAUAUAAUAAUAAUGAAAUAUAGCUUUUUUUUUCAACUCAGAAAUCCUAUUCCCUCUCCCCAUCUGUGAUUAUAUUGUACUGGACUUCUGACUUGGUCAAAAGCAUAGGUUUUGACUUAGAUACAUGUGGGGGCAGAUCUCAGCUCUAUCACUAACUAGCUAUAUGAUAUUUGGCAAGUUUUUUCUCUAUGUGCAGUAGUUUCUUUAUCUGUAAAAUUAAGAUAAUAGCUACUUUACAGGGUUGGAAGAAUUAAUUUAGAAAUUGUACAGUGCUUAGCCUCAAUAAUUGGUAGGUGGUGGUGUAAAUAUUUUACAUAGAUACUUGUGACAGUUCUUUGUUCUACAAAACAGACUAAUAUUAAUUUCAGAUUGGCCAAGCUACUUAAUUUCUCUGUGCCUCAGUUUCCUCACUAUUAAAUGGGGAUGACAAUAGUGUCCACCUAGAGCAGGACUAUUUUAGUAUUACAUAUAAUCCUUGGAUAUAAAUGCUGAUGAAGUUUGGAUAUUUGUCCCCACCCAAGUCUCAUGUUGAAAUGUAAUCCCCAAUCUUGGAGGUGGAGCCUGGUGGGAGGUGUAUGGAUUAGAUCAGAUCUCUCAUGAAUGACUUGGGCCAUCCUUUGGGUGGUAAGUGAGCUCUUGCUCCGAGUUCACACGAGGUCUAGAUCUGGUCAUUUAAAAGUGUGUGGCAUCUCCCCAUCCCUCACUCUAUCACUUGCUCCUACUUUCGUCAUAUGACAUGCCUGCUCCCCUUUCACCUUCUGCCAUGAUUGUAAGCUUCCUGAGGCCUCCCUAGAAGCUGAGCAGAUGCCAGCACCAUGCUUCCUGUAGUCUGUAGAACCAUAAGCCAAAUAAACAUCUUUUCUUUAUAAAUUUAUAAAUUACCCAGUCGCAGAUAUUUAUAGAAAGAACAGCCUAAUACAGGUGCUAAAUACAUAUCUGACAAUAAAUGGUAGUUAUCUCUUAGAACUGUUAUGAGGAUUAAACGAGUUACAGUGUCCAUCUUAAAAAGAUAAUUCUGAAAAAAAUCUCAUAGGUUCACUUUGCCUUGUCAAGAAUAUGAUUACCAUUAACUUCUGUAGAUAGGAAAAAAAUGUGCUGAGCUCCAAAACUGACAGACAUUUUGCUAAAACAAUAUCAAAUCUCAUUAAAAUGAUGACAGUUAUUUCAAUAGUUGACAGUAGCUAUCCCAAUACAACCUAACAAGGCAUUUUCUCUUCAGAAUCACUCGAUCAUAUGGCCAUUUCCCUAAGCUUUUAUAGCUAUUGCCCAGUGUACACUGAAGACAACAGCUAACGAACAACAUACGUGUGAUAAUUUAUGUAGUUGAACCUCUAAGGCAAAAAAAAAAAAAAAAAGGAAAAAUUAGUGAAAAUCAUUCAAACAUUAUGCUCACCAGGUAGACUGCCAUCAUAGAAGUCCUAAUGCUACUGCUAAAAACUAGUAAACUACCAGUAAACUGUGAAGACAGAAGUAACUCCUGUGAUCUAUAUGUUUGUGCAGAUGGUGGAGCUUUUCUGCUCCUAAAGCCUGAGAAAUGCAAAUGUGGCUUCGUUAAUGCAAAUGCUUCCUACGCCAGACUUUAUGAAACUCCUCCUAAAGUUGAAUUCUUAUCCAAGUGGACAUAUGUUAGGGUGCCAUUGUAAUUCAGGUAGAGUGUCAGAGUGGUGGCUGGCACCAACGGUAGAUGUUCUCAACAUUAGCGUUAUUCAGGUAAGACUACAACAAUGAUGAACAUGUCAAAACUUUCCUUUAAAAGGAACAAUCAGAAAAACUCUUUAACAAAUGUUUUUCUUUCCGUAGUAUUUUAAUUAAAAUUUUUAAAAUUUUAAAAUUUACUAAAUUUAUGAACGUUUUUAUCCCACUUGAGAUGAAUACUUAUUUAUAGUCCCUGUCCCAUGAAGCUUCUGUGGAUUUGCUUUGUUUGUCAUUUGUGGUAUGUUUGAUAACAAAAAUAUUAGUGGCACAAAAGCAGUUAUAUUGAAUGCUUUUGUUUUAGAGAAAAUUUCACUCUGUACUAGAAAAUGUAGAUGAUGUGAGUCAAAGUUCAUUAAUAUUUACCUGAAAAUUUGUGUAUAAAGGUAACCUUGGGGCAGUUUAUUUUGCUUAGACCCCUCAGCUUCUUGAUAGAGUGAGGUGAGGGCAUAUGUAAGUCAGUAAACUAUUCUGUUAGUAAAGUCAAAGGCGUAAUCUAAAUUAAUUAUGCUUUUAACUAACACAGAAGAAAUCAUGUGACCUCAUUCUCAAAGCUCGUAACAUCCACCUGGCCAAUCUUAAGAUGUGGAUAGAGUUCUUUUUUUUCUUUUUUCAAUUUUUACAAUAAUUUUUGACACAUUGAAGCUGUGCAUGUUUAUGGGGGCACAAUUUGAUGUUUCAAUACAUGUAUAUGUUGUGUAAUGAUCAAAUCGGAGUACUUAGCAUAUCUAUCAUCUCGUGCAUUUAUCAUUUCUUUGUGGCGAGAACAUUUAAAAAUCCUAUUUUCUAGCUAUUUUGUAAUAUACACUACCUUACUGUUGCGAACCAUAGUCACCCUACUGUGCAAUAGAACACCUGAACUUAUUCCUCCUAUCUAGUUGUAACUUUGUACCCAUUGACCCCCCUUCCCUUCCUUCCACUCUCCCCUCCCCAGUCUCUGGUAACCACUGUUCUGUUCCCUAUGAGAUAAAACUUUUUUUGUCUUCCA